AAACAGAGUGAAGACACUGGCCCUGGCAGGCAGCAGCUGGGUCUAAGAGAGCUGCAGCCCAGGGUCACAGACCUGUGGGCCCCAUGGCCGGGAAGGCGGCAGAGGAGAGAGGGCUGCCGAAAGGGGCCACUCCCCAGGAUACCUCGGGCCUCCAGGAUAGAUUGUUCUCCUCUGAAAGUGACAACAGCCUGUACUUCACCUACAGUGGCCAGCCCAACACCCUGGAGGUCAGAGACCUCAACUACCAGGUGGACCUGGCCUCUCAGGUCCCUUGGUUUGAGCAGCUGGCUCAGUUCAAGAUGCCCUGGACAUCUCCCAGCUGCCAGAAUUCUUGUGAGCUGGGCAUCCAGAACCUAAGCUUCAAAGUGAGAAGUGGGCAGAUGCUGGCCAUCAUAGGGAGCUCAGGUUGUGGGAGAGCCUCCUUGCUAGAUGUGAUCACUGGCCGAGGUCACGGCGGCAAGAUCAAGUCAGGCCAGAUCUGGAUCAAUGGGCAGCCCAGCUCGCCUCAGCUGGUGAGGAAGUGUGUGGCCCACGUGCGCCAGCACAACCAGCUGCUCCCCAACUUGACUGUGCGAGAGACCUUGGCCUUCAUUGCCCAGAUGCGGCUGCCCAGAACCUUCUCCCAGGCCCAGCGUGACAAAAGGGUGGAGGACGUGAUCGCGGAGCUGCGGCUUAGGCAGUGCGCUGACACCCGCGUGGGCAACAUGUACGUGCGGGGGUUGUCGGGGGGUGAGCGCAGGAGAGUCAGCAUUGGGGUGCAGCUCCUGUGGAACCCAGGAAUCCUUAUUCUCGACGAACCCACCUCUGGGCUCGACAGCUUCACAGCCCACAACCUGGUGAAGACCUUGUCCAGGCUGGCCAAAGGCAACCGGCUGGUGCUCAUCUCCCUCCACCAGCCUCGCUCUGACAUCUUCAGGCUGUUUGAUCUGGUCCUCCUGAUGACGUCUGGCACCCCCAUCUACUUAGGGGCGGCCCAGCACAUGGUCCAGUAUUUCACAGCCAUCGGCUACCCCUGUCCUCGCUACAGCAAUCCUGCUGACUUCUAUGUGGACCUGACCAGCAUUGACAGGCGCAGCAGAGAGCAGGAAUUGGCCACCAGGGAGAAGGCUCAGUCACUCGCAGCCCUGUUUCUAGAAAAAGUGCGUGACUUAGAUGACUUUCUAUGGAAAGCAGAGACGAAGGAUCUUGACGAGGACACCUGUGUGGAAAGCAGCGUGACCCCACUAGACACCAACUGCCUCCCGAGUCCUACGAAGAUGCCUGGGGCGGUGCAGCAGUUUACGACGCUGAUCCGUCGUCAGAUUUCCAACGACUUCCGAGACCUGCCCACCCUCCUCAUCCAUGGGGCGGAGGCCUGUCUGAUGUCAAUGACCAUCGGCUUCCUCUAUUUUGGCCAUGGGAGCAUCCAGCUCUCCUUCAUGGAUACAGCCGCCCUCUUGUUCAUGAUCGGUGCUCUCAUCCCUUUCAACGUCAUUCUGGAUGUCAUCUCCAAAUGUUACUCAGAGAGGGCAAUGCUUUACUAUGAACUGGAAGACGGGCUGUACACCACUGGUCCAUAUUUCUUUGCCAAGAUCCUCGGGGAGCUUCCGGAGCACUGUGCCUACAUCAUCAUCUACGGGAUGCCCACCUACUGGCUGGCCAACCUGAGGCCAGGCCUCCAGCCCUUCCUGCUGCACUUCCUGCUGGUGUGGCUGGUGGUCUUCUGUUGCAGGAUUAUGGCCCUGGCCGCCGCGGCCCUGCUCCCCACCUUCCACAUGGCCUCCUUCUUCAGCAAUGCCCUCUACAACUCCUUCUACCUCGCCGGGGGCUUCAUGAUAAACUUGAGCAGCCUGUGGACAGUGCCCGCGUGGAUUUCCAAAGUGUCCUUCCUGCGGUGGUGUUUUGAAGGGCUGAUGAAGAUUCAGUUCAGCAGAAGAACUUAUAAAAUGCCUCUCGGGAACCUCACCAUCGCGGUCUCAGGAGAUAAAAUCCUCAGUGUCAUGGAGCUGGACUCGUACCCUCUCUACGCCAUCUACCUCAUCGUCAUUGGCCUCAGCGGUGGCUUCAUGGUCCUGUACUACGUGUCCUUAAGGUUCAUCAAACAGAAACCAAGUCAAGACUGGUGAUUCACGCCAGACGUCUGCCCGCUGGUGGGGGACCUGAGCAGACCCUUCAACUGCACUCCCUCCUCAGGAGCCCCUUCCUGGGGACAGUGAGGACAAUGACCCUACAGAUGCUCAGCUACAUCCGGCCCAGGGUGCUGCAGUGGCACAGACCAGCCACAGGAUGGCAGUAGAAUAAAGACAGUCGAAAGGGAUUUCUGCUCACUGGCAGGAGACUGCGAUGACUGGGAGAAAACCUGCACUCGGUGGCACCUACAACGUUGCUAAUUUAUUUCCUUUUGAUAUGCAUUUAUAUAGGCAACUCGAUAUAGGAUGGGAGCAAACUAGGAAUGAAUUGGGUAGCUAGACUGUGCAGGAAUUGUUGGAACCUGGAGGGAACAAUAACAGUAGCUAGCAGAUUUGGCUUCAUCUUCCAGGGGCCCCACACUCCGUGGUGAGCCACCAUCAAUACAGAAAGUGACCUAAGAUGUACCAGCAAGAUGCCAUCCCUUCUUUUUGUGUGGGGUCAUGGGCUCCAAAAGCCAACGUGAACAAUUAAAAAUGUAUUGAGCAUCUACUCUGUAGCAGGUCCUGUGAAAACACUUUAGGUGGACAAUCCCUUGAGGUAAGUGGUAUCCCAUUUUAUAGGUGUGAAAACUGAAGCAAAAAUUCAUUUUCCUAAGGGCACAUGGAUACUUUGUGGUGGAGUCAUAUGGGGAUCAGAAAAGCCUUUGAGGCCUUUGGAGUUAGAGGGCAGAAGGCAAGGCCUGAGCCGCUGUAAGCCUUAGGAGUUUAGGAAGGCUCCAGAAGACAAAUGGGGUCUGUAGAGGCUGUUAACUCAGCCAGGCUUCUUAGAGUUGCAUUUCACUAACUGAUAUGGUUUGGCUCUGCGUCCUCACCCAAAUCUCACCUUGAAUUGUAAUAAUCCCCAAGUGUCAAGGGCGGGACCAGAUGGAGAUAAUUGAAUCAUAGGGGUGGUUUCUCUGAUGCUGUUCUCCUGAGAGUGAGUGAGUUCUGAUGAGAUCCGACGGUUUUAUAAGGGGCUUCCCUCUUCGCUCGGCUCUCAUUCUCUCUCCCGCUACCCUGUGAAGAGGAGCCUUCCACCACGACUGCAAGUUUCCUGAGGCUGCCCCAGCCGUGCUGAACUGUGAGUCAGUUAAACCUCUUUUCUUUAUAAAUUACCCAGUCUUGGGUAUUUCUUCAUAGCAGUGUGAGAGCAGAUGAAUACACUGGCCCUGCCUGGGUUUCAGAACCAGCCUUGAACCUUUCACAGUGGCCAGAGGAUGGGGAGGCAGAGGCCCAGGUUGCACACUUCUUGCCUGAGUGUUGGGGACUAUCUGACCCAAAACAGGUGCACAGAGGGCAGGAGAGGAUGUUCCCAAAGGAAAAUUAGAGUUUAGAAUCAAAAGAAGGGGAAGGUGCGUGUUUGGGAGGUAAAUAGCAAAUACUCUUCAUAGGUUCACUAGAGUCUUGCUACUCCAAGUACGAUCCCUGGGCCAGCAGAAUGGGCACAGCUGGAGCUGAUUGGAUAGGUCCCAUGAGCCUCAGGCCCCACCCAGGCUCAAUGAGUCAGAGUCUGCGUCUUAAGAAGACCCCCUGGUGAUCUGUGCACAUUCAAGCAUGCUGCCGUUUUCCAAAGCACUUGCAACACUCAGGAUGCUUGCACGGUCAUGUUGCCACCAUCCAACCUGCAGACCCCAUUCUUGAGAUUGACUGGGAGUUCCUAUCAUGUCCUCCAUAGCAAGGGGAUCUAGACCAGAAUCAAGCCUUGGAUCUAGUUCUCAAGUCUCUUUUGUCUCUUUCAGUUUAGGAACAGUUUGUCAACUUUCCUUCACUUUUGUGACCUUGAUACUUGAGUUUGAAGGCUGUCUCUCAAUUUGUGUUCUGCCCAGUGCAUCCUAUCAGAAGGCAUGUGAUUUCAACUUCUCCCAUACCAACAACGUUCACUUUGAUCACUUGAUUAAAGGGGUGUCUGCUAGGCUUCUCCACAGCCAAGUUACUAUUUUCCCUCCCUUUAUAAUUAAUAAGCAUUUUGUAAGUGGGUACUUUGAAACUAUGUAAAUUGUAAACUUUCCAUUUAUGCAUUUUAAAAUUUUGAUUGAUGUAAACUUGUGAAUUCCCAUUGUAUCCUUACAACCCUUUAUUAUUGUGAUUAAUUCUGAUGCUCAGCUUGUCCCUGAUUUGGCCAGUGGGAACCCCGUCGAGCUGGCUUCUGCAUCCUUUUGAUAUGUCCUCAUCAUCCUUUGAGGGCUGAAACAACCAAGAGUUUCAGGCUCAUUUUUUGUUUUGUUUUUUUUUUUUUGAGACAGAAUCUCAUUCUGUGGCCCAGGCUGGAGUGCAAUGGCGCGAUCUCGGCUCACUGCAACCUCUGCCUCCCAGGUUCAAGCGAUUGCCUUGCCUCAGCCUCCCAAGUAGUUGGGAUUAACAGUGCCCACCACCACACCUGGCUAAUUUUUGUAUUUUUAGUAAAGACAGUGUUUCACCAUAUUGGCCAGACUGGUUGUGAACUCUAGGCCUCAAGUGAUCUGCCUGCUUCGGCCUCCCAAAGUGUUGGGAUUACAGGUGUGACCCACCGCACCUGGUGUCACAGGUUCAUCUUGUAUUUUCCCAUCUCAGCCCUGGAAUCCGAUGUUUCUCCAGAGAAUCUGGGUUCCUCUUAGUGGAAAAUGGUAUUUAGAAGCCAAGGUUUUGGUGAUAAGUAUGCUCUUUGCUUGUGGAACAUCUCUGCUCCCAGGCUCUCUCAGUGAACAGAGUUAGGGAGUGUGUGUGUGUGUGCGCGCGCGCGCGCGCAUGUGCAUACAUAUACACCUAAGUACACAUGAGUUUACUCUGAUAACAUCCAUUUCCAAUCCAGCAUCACAGAGUUGAUCCUAGGUUCUUCCCUCUUCUCUAAUUGUGAGAAACCUGGCUUCCAUUACCCUUAGGUUAUUUACUCAUUUGAUUAACCGCCUGCAGGUAAGUAAUCUCCCAUCUACACUGCCACGCCUUCUCCUGUAUGGACGUCCUGCCUACCCUGCUCAGGCUCUAACUCCCAAGUCCAGCUUUCCCUGAGUCUGCAGCUGUCUUCCUCACACUCCCGUGGCCCACCACAACUUCCCCCCACCUCCUUGUCACUGUGGUCCCCUAAUGGCGUUAGGCCUGAAUGAAGAAGGGGGAAGGAUGAAGAGGACAUUGGUAGCUUGCCUUAACUCCCCAGGUAAUUCUAAUGUGCAGUGAUUGACAGCCACUAAGAUACAUCACCUGACUUUGUGAGUUCACCAUUCGGUCUGCAAUGGGUUUUGGUAACUCAGUGGCUCUGUAUGCCGUGCUGAAGGGGAAAAGGGCAAAGUGCAAAGGCAGGAGGGAUGGAGAAAAUAUAGCAGCUGCCAUUUAUUUGUGUUUUUCCUACAGCGGUGGUUCUCCACCCUGGUUGCCCAUGCUGGAGCUUUAACAAAAGCCAAUGUGGACCCAUUGCCCAGAGACUCUGAUCCCAUGGGUCUGUUUUGUUUAAAAUGCUCUUCAAGGCAUUGUGAGGCCAGGAAAACAAAGAACCAAGGCUCUCCCGGGUGCGGUGGCUCACGCCUGUAAUCCCAGCACUUUGGGAGGCCGCGGAGGGCAGAUCACGAGGUCAGGAGAUCGAGACCAUUCUGGCCAACAUGGCAAAACCCUGCCUCUACUAAAAAUACAAAAAUUAGCUGGGCAUGGUAGUGCGUGCCUGUAGUUCCAGCUACUUGGGAGGUUGAGGCAGGAGAAUCGCUUGAAUCCGGGAGGCAGAGGUUGCAGUGAGCCGAGAUUGAGCCACCGCACUCCAGCCUGGUGACAGAGCGAUACUCUGUCUCAAAAAAAAAAAAAAAAAACCCAAGGCUCUCGAGGCAUGCAUGCUGUUCAGCGAGCCCUGCCCUGCAUUGCGAAAGGGUAGAGAUUUGUUUAUUUGUCAGUAUUGAAAGCAUGGCUUGCAAAGUUUUCCUGUUAAGAGUCAGAUAGUAAAUAUUUGGGACUUCGUGGGCCUUAUAGGCUCUGCUGCAAUUACUUAACUCUGCUGUUACAGUGUGAGAGCAGCUGUAGACUAUAGUAACGUACAGCCGGUGUGGCUGUCUUCUAAGAAAGUAUUAUUUACAAAAACAGGCAGGUUGCUAGAUUUGACCUGAGGGUGUAGUUUGCAGAGCCUUGGUAAAGGUUUUCAAAUUUGCAUUUUAAGCCCUCCAAUUUCAAGUUAUGCUAUUGGUGGGGAAUUUUAAUUAAACAGAAAAUAAUCACCAAUAUUGGCUCAAAUAUUUCCUGAUUUAAAAAAAAAUCUGCUCUUGUUCCUAUAAAUAGUAUAUAAGAUGUAAUCUUGCCCUGGGUUAAACCAGUCUACAGAGGUAGAUCUCGCAUUUGCUUUUGUUUUCUUCUACUUCAACUCUUGUCAUGAUCCCAAAUUAAACAACUAGCAACAGAAAUGUUCAAAUCUGUCAAAUCCAAGUGUUAACAGACCUGGGACCAGGGGUUCCUCAUAGUGGCUUAGCACAGCAUACAGACCACUUUCCUUUGGCCCAACCGGCCUUGGGGUCUGGAGCACCAAACAGGCCCUGAGGAAGCGUGCAAGGAACUGGAAUGCGGGGAAAGUGAUGAAAUAUUUUGUUGGUUGGCCUUUGCUUGUUUGCAAAAUAUAUCCAAUGCUCACACCUGAGAGACAACAGACAUCCUUAUUUGUGAAUAGUCUGCACUAGAUAAUUCAGAUUUCAAGUCAUCUGUCAUUCGUACUUGAUAAUGAUUUGUUCUUCAUUUAAAGUGGCCUGGGUACAGAGCAACAUCCCCUGUCUUUAUCACAUGAGCUCUGCCUGAGGCAGCUUCAGCAGGUAGGCAGGCAGGCAGAUGGAGCACAGCCCAUUCUCUGCUGGUGCACUAGGAACAGCAGCACGUGUGGUGUUAGCAGCUAAUAAUUAAAACAACGUUUAAGCAGUGGGUUGAGAUUUUUAAACACAAACCAACUCAAAAACACUUCUCUGCUUUCUAUGUAAUAGUGCUCACAUCAUUUGUAUGAUUGUCUCGUCUCUUUAAAAUUGGAAAUAUUCUUGUUUCCCCAAACUGCUAAUAAGCUCUACUGACCCAUGCUAAAAAUAAAGCUCUUUCGGCUGGGC